GAGAACGGAAGAGGCGGCGCGCCGGUUGAGCAGGGCGUCUCUAGGCCUGGUCGGCUGGCGGCGGUGAGUGGGCCCCAGGCAAGGGCGGAGGGCGGAACUUUGGGGUUCGGCACUGCCGGGCGGCCGGAAGGUACGGUGGGGAUAGCUCUCUGGGCGCGCGAGGCAGAGAAGGGGACCGGGCUGGGACUGUACACUGGGCCUCAGUCCCUCAAAUCCGGGACCGGGCGUCCGCAGCUCGGCUGGCCGGGACUCCCUUCGGGACGCUGAGGAGGAAGGGGAAGGUGUGGGCCCUGCUCCUUCGGGACGCCCCAGGCUGGCCAGCAGCUCACACAUCCGCAUUGCGCCCUCUGAUCCCAGCGUUGGGGCGGAUAGCUAGCGUUGGGCCUGCCCCUGUUUUGGGGCAGUCGCCCAAACGACGCCGCACGCCUAGUGGCGAGCUGAACCCAGACUAGGACACCCGAAGACCAAAUGGAUAGAGUGAGAAGGAAAUGGGGGUUAGCAACCUGAAUUGAGGUACUGGAUUCCAAGUGACAGCUUCACAAGCUGAAAUCUUGUAGGAUGGCAGGAUUUUCAUAAUAUAUGUAGUAUGAGUUCCACAUCUUGGCCUCUUACCCAGCUUCAGCAGUCUCAGCUCCACCAGUUAGAGAAUAAAUGGGAUUUGCAUGAACUCCACUCUGAGCUGAAAUACAGACUGCGGUGUUAAUAUCCUUUUCUUCUGAUUGUUAUUAACAGGUCCUUAUGUCGUCAGAAGAUCGAGAAGCUCAGGAGGAUGAAUUGCUGGCCCUGGCAAGUAUUUACGAUGGAGAUGAAUUUAGAAAAGCAGAGUCUGUCCAAGGUGGAGAAACCAGGAUCUAUUUGGAUUUGCCACAGAAUUUCAAGAUAUUUGUGAGCGGCAAUUCAAAUGAGUGUCUCCAGAAUAGUGGCUUUGAAUACACCAUUUGCUUUCUGCCUCCACUUGUGCUGAACUUUGAACUGCCACCAGAUUAUCCAUCCUCUUCCCCACCUUCAUUCACACUUAGUGGCAAAUGGCUGUCACCAACUCAGCUAUCUGCUCUAUGCAAGCACUUAGACAACCUAUGGGAAGAACACCGUGGCAGCGUGGUCCUGUUUGCCUGGAUGCAAUUUCUUAAGGAAGAGACCCUAGCAUACUUGAAUAUUGUCUCUCCUUUUGAGCUCAAGAUUGGUUCUCAGAAAAAAGUGCAGAGAAGGACAGCUCAAGCUUCUCCCAACACAGAGCUAGAUUUUGGAGGAGCUGCUGGAUCUGAUGUAGACCAAGAGGAAAUUGUGGAUGAGAGAGCAGUGCAGGAUGUGGAAUCACUGUCAAAUCUGAUCCAGGAAAUCUUGGACUUUGAUCAAGCUCAGCAGAUAAAAUGCUUUAAUAGUAAAUUGUUCCUGUGCAGUAUCUGUUUCUGUGAGAAGCUGGGUAGUGAAUGCAUGUACUUCUUGGAGUGCAGGCAUGUGUACUGCAAAGCCUGUCUGAAGGACUACUUUGAAAUCCAGAUCAGAGAUGGCCAGGUUCAAUGCCUCAACUGCCCAGAACCAAAGUGCCCUUCGGUGGCCACUCCUGGUCAGGUCAAAGAGUUAGUGGAAGCAGAGUUAUUUGCCCGUUAUGACCGCCUUCUCCUCCAGUCCUCCUUGGACCUGAUGGCAGAUGUGGUGUACUGCCCCCGGCCGUGCUGCCAGCUGCCUGUGAUGCAGGAACCUGGCUGCACCAUGGGUAUCUGCUCCAGCUGCAAUUUUGCCUUCUGUACUUUGUGCAGGUUGACCUACCAUGGGGUCUCCCCAUGUAAGGUGACUGCAGAGAAAUUAAUGGACUUACGAAAUGAAUACCUGCAAGCGGAUGAGGCUAAUAAAAGACUUUUGGAUCAAAGGUAUGGUAAGAGAGUGAUUCAGAAGGCACUGGAAGAGAUGGAAAGUAAGGAGUGGCUAGAGAAGAACUCAAAGAGCUGCCCAUGUUGUGGAACUCCCAUAGAGAAAUUAGACGGAUGUAACAAGAUGACAUGUACUGGCUGUAUGCAAUAUUUCUGUUGGAUUUGCAUGGGUUCUCUCUCUAGAGCAAACCCUUACAAACAUUUCAAUGACCCUGGUUCACCAUGUUUUAACCGGCUGUUUUAUGCUGUGGAUGUUGACGACGAUAUUUGGGAAGAUGAGGUAGAAGACUAGUUAACUACUGCUCAAGAUAUGGAAGUGGAUUGUUUUUCCCUAAUCUUCCGUCAAGUACACAAAGUAACUUUGCGGGAUAUUUAGGGUACUAUUCAUUCACUCUUCCUGCGUAGAAGAUAUGGAAGAACGAGGUUUAUAUUUUCAUGUGGUACUACUGAAGAAGGUGCAUUGAUACAUUUUUAAAUGUAAGUUGAGAAAAAUUUAUAAGCCAAAGGUUCAGAAAAUUAAACUACAGAAUAUUAAAUAUUAUAAUGUGCCCAAAGCUCUGAAUAGUUAAAAAUUAAAUAUUUAUUUUCUUCCCCAAGCUUUAGGUAAGGAGAAGAGGGGUCAAGAGUUAAACUUAGAGACCCUUUGUCUCUGAGAAGCAUCCUUCUAAGACAUUCUGUUGGAGUUCCCUCAGUACUAUUCCUUACAACUGGAGUGGGUAGAAGCCUUAUGAAAAUUAUACUGAGAACCUGAUCUCGUUUACUCCAUGUUAAUCACAUUCCUACCAACCUAAAUUUCUGCCAAGUCAGUUCUCUUUGGAGGAAGCCCAUUACUCCGUAACUGACUGGAUGGUCCAGUGUCAUUUUGAUCUGCUUUUCAGAAUGGAAAUUUAUAAUAUAAAUAUAUGUUUUAAUACCACAAACACUGUGGGGCACUUGAUAUUUAUUAGUGGUGUAUAUGGUCCACUGGUUUCAGGCCAAAUCUAGAAUUUAGUGAUACUGGCUCAGAAGAAUUUAAGUUCUAUUCAGCCUUCCUGGGUGUUAGAACCUAGAUUCAAAAUGGCUUGUCUUUGCUACUUUUGUUCCACAUUCUCUCUCUUUACCUUUGCCCUACCUUCUGUUUGUAAGGAUGAUUUUAAUAUUAAUUCCAGGAACACAUGUUUUUAUUUCCUCUGCUGGAAUAGGAGAAAGCUUAAUAUAUUCCCAAGCUGAAUGUUCUUGAAUUAUAUCUGCAUUUACCACUGUAUAUGCAUAUAGUGACAGUAUAACCUGUCUAUACUACAGUAGUUCCAGUCCUAACUUUCUGAAUUAUUUUUAAAGAUCUUCUCUAACAAGCUAUGGGAAUUUGGCUUCAUACUCUUUCUUUGCAACAGCAGUGUUCUGGGUGAUAAUUUUGAAUUGAUACCUGUUCCUUUUUCUGGGUUUUGUUGGCUUUUUGAAAAAUUGUCUUUCCUUAUCAUUGGUGGGAGGCUUGGUAGCAAAGUAACAUUUUUUGGAAAAGAGGACAGAAAAAUUGAACUACAGCUUGAGAACGUAUUCUUUUUUUCCUACUUUGUUAUUGCAAAUUGAGGAAUCACUUUUAACUGUUUUAGGUGUGUGUGUCCAGAGUGAGCAAGGAUUAUGUUUUUGGAUUGUCAAAGAGGAUGCUUAGUCUUAAAAUAAAAAUAAAUUUAAAAAUCAUCUUAUAAUUAGAACAGAGUUGCUGCUAUUUGUUCUGUCACCAAGGCAACUAAUCACAUUUUAAAACUGUUCGGCAUAUAACAUAUUCUUAAAGUAAGAAAAAAAAGGUCACAGAAUAGCAUCUCUUUUACCUGGGCUUGUGACUGAGCUUAGGUUUUAGGGCCCAUAUUUUGUUUAAACCAGAUAGUUUCAUGGUCUUCCAUUCAGGACAUUUUGUGUAAAAAUUGAGGUUAAUUUGCUGGGCACAGUGGCUCACGCCUGUAAUCCCAGCACUUUGGGAGGCCUAGGCGGGCGGAUCACGAGGUCAGGAGUUCGAGACCAUCAUGGCUAACACGGUGAAACCCCGUCUCUACUAAAAAUACAAAAAAUUAGCUGGGCAUGGUGGCAGGCGCCUGUAGUCCCAGCUACUCAGGAGGCUGAGGCAGGAGAAUGGCAUGAACCUGGGAGGUGGAGCUUGCAGUGAGCCGAGAUAGCGCCACUGCACUCCAGCCUGAGCGACAGAGCGAGACUCCUUCUCAAAAAAAAAAAAAAAAAAAAUUGAGGUUAAAGAAUAAAUUAAAGAUAAGAAAUGGAAAUUAAAAUGAUUUGUUCUACAGUAUAUACCUGAGAAGAGUGAUUUCUGUGAUCAAAGAGUUCAAUUCAGAUUUAUUCAGAAAGAGCUACUCAGAAGCUCUAUAGUUCGUGAGCUACUUGAUAUUUUCUAGAGAUCAUUUUAUGUUAAGCUGUUAUACAUUGUUGAUGAUGUCAUAGAAGUAGGAAAGAAGCCUUUAUAAUACAGUUUUAUGAAAGAAAUGGGAGCCUUUUUUCCCAUUUAUGAUAUUAAAAACAACACAGGUAUUUGGUGUUUAGUCUCAAAAAUUUGUUUGGUCACCUUAGUGAUUCUUAGGUACAAAGUCUUCAUCACUCAAUUUUAACAAAGAAAAUAGGGCUUAUAAAGUUAUACUUUUGAAGCAUGAGUUAUGAGCUAAUUUUAAGAUGUAUAGUUUUGGUAGAGUACUUUUGUCUCAGUAAAAUGAAAGAUUUGGGUAACUCCCCAAAUGCCCUGUAAAACAAAUGGGUUUGUGGAAGGUUGUGGUGUCAGCAAAAUAUAUGAUAGAAUAAAGAGUUUUGUACCUAC